CACCACCCUUCACCACACACUCCCCACCUACAGAGAGCAGUCCCCUCUCUCCCACAGGUCCUAUGACUCCAACAUCCUUCAAGACCACCACUACCUAUCCAACCACAUCACACCCUCAGACCACACUUCCCACUCACGUUCCACCUUUCUCCAGCUCGUCAGUGACUCCAAGUACUCACACAGUCAUCACCCCUACCCAUGCACAGAUGUCCACUUCUGCCUCGAUCCACUCAACGCCAACAGGUACCAUUCCUCCACUGACAACGCUCACGGCCACAGGGUCCACACACACAGCCUCACCAAUGACGGGGACAACCAUUCGGACCACCCAAGCCCACAGCUCAUUCAGCAUAGCCAAAACCUCUACAUCCAUCCUCUCACAUGCUUCCUCCACACACCAUCCGGAAACCACACCAACUUCUACCACCAACAUUACUCCCAAGUCCACUAGUGCAGGAACCAGCACCCCUGUGGCCCACACCACCUUGGCCACCAGCAGCAGGCCACCCACACCCUUCACCACACACUCCCCACCUACAGGGAGCAGUCCCAUCUCUUCCACAGGUCCUAUGACUGCAACAUCCAUCAAGACCACCACGACCUAUCCAACCCCAUCACACCCUCAGACCACACUUACCACUCAUGUUCCACCUUUCUCCACCUCAUCAGUCACUCCAAGUACUCACACAGUCAUCACCCCUACCCACGCACAGAUGUCCACUUCCUCCACACACUAUCCUGAAGUCACCCCAACUUCUACCACCACCAUCACCCCCAACCACACCAACCACCACUACCUAUCCAACACCAUCACACCCUCAGACCACACAUCCCACUCACGUUACAUCUUUCUCCACCUCCUUGGUGACUCCAAGUACUCACACAGUCAUCACCCCUACCCACGCACAGAUGGCCACUUAUGCGUCCAUCCACUCAACGCCAACAGGCACCAUUUCUCCACCAACAACGCUCAAGGCCACAGGGUCCUUCCCCUCAGCCCCACCAAUGACGUCGACCACCAGUGGGACCAGCCAAUCCCGAAGCUCAUUUAG